ACUUUGCGCGCGGCCUCUGGAGCUCCAGCUGCGCCCCGCCACCACUGGCCGCUCGCACUACCAGCCUGUCUCGCACGCUAAGGUCACGACCGCUGCAAGCAGGCUUUGCUGCAGAUUGGGAUCAACAUGAUGGCACUGCCUGGAGGUCGCCACCUGGACUCCGUCACCCUGCCGGGUCAGCGGCUACACCUGAUGCAGGUGGACUCAGUCCAGCGCUGGAUGGAAGAUCUGAAGCUCAUGACCGAGUGCGAGUGCAUGUGUGUCCUGCAGGCCAAGCCCAUCAGCCUGGAAGAGGAUGCACAGGGUGACCUCAUCCUGGCAGGUGGCCCUGGCCCUGGAGACCCCCUGCAGCUGCUGCUCAAACGGGGUUGGGUCAUUAGCACAGAGCUGCGCAGGAUCGGGCAGAAGCUGGCCCAGGACCGCUGGGCACGGGUGCACAGCAUGAGCGUGCGUCUGACCUGCCAUGCCCGCUCCAUGGUCAGCGAGUACAGUGCUGUCAGCAGGAACUCCUUGAAGGAAAUGGGCGAGAUUGAGAAGCUGCUAAUGGAGAAAUGCUCGGAGCUCUCGGCAGUCACAGAGAGGUGCCUUCAGGUUGAGAAUGAGCAUGUCCUGAAGUCAAUGAAGGCCUGCGUGAGUGAGACCCUGAGCAUGCUGGGCCAGCACUUUGGUCAGCUGCUGGAGCUGGCCCUGACACGGGAGGUUCAGGCACUGGUGAGAAAAAUUGAUGCCUCAGACAAUAUCUACACCACAGAGUCCACCACAGGGAACCUGUUCAGCCUGACCCAGGAGGGGGCUCCCUUGUGCCGCAUCAUAGCCAAGGAGGGUGGGGUCGUAGCACUCUUCAAGGUUUGCCGGCAGGACAGUUUCCGGUGCUUGUACCCCCAGGCGCUCCGCACGCUGGCCUCCAUCUGCUGCGUGGAAGAGGGUGUCCACCAGCUGGAGAAGGUGGAUGGCGUUCUGUGCUUGGCCGACAUCCUGACCGACAACAGCCACUCAGAGGCCACACGGGCUGAGGCUGCGGCUGUGGUGGCCCAGGUCACCUCCCCACACCUGCCCGUCACCCAGCACCUCAGUAGCUUCCUGGAGAGCAUGGAGGAGAUCGUGACAGCCCUCGUCAAACUGUGCCAAGAGGCCUCAUCAGGGGAAGUCUUCCUACUGGCCUCUGCGGCCCUUGCCAACAUCACGUUCUUUGACACAAUGGCCUGCGAGAUGCUCCUGCAGUUGAAUGCCAUCCGUGUUCUCCUGGAAGCCUGCAGUGACAAGCAGAGAGUGGACACGCCUUACACUCGGGACCAGAUUGUGACCAUCUUGGCAAACAUGUCUGUCCUAGAACAGUGUGCCUCUGACAUCAUUCAGGAAAAUGGGGUCCAGCUUAUCAUGGGCAUGCUGUCUGAAAAACCAAGGUCUGGGACUCCUGCUGAAGUGGCAGCCUGUGAGCGAGUCCAGCAGAAAGCUGCAGUGACCCUGGCUCGUCUCAGCCGAGACCCAGAUGUGGCACGGGAGGCCGUGCGGCUCAGCUGCAUGUCCCGUCUCAUCGAGCUCUGCAGAUCCCCAUCAGAGAGGAACAGCAGUGACGCCGUGCUUGUGGCCUGCCUGGCUAUGGGGAUACAGCUGCAGGUAAAAAAGACAAACAUCUCUGCCCUCCUGCUGUGGUUUUUAUUUUGGCACAUUCAAGGUAAUCUUAAUCUUUUUGUAUCUUUGGUACUCUGGUGAAGCUUACGGAGCCCUUCUCAGAAUAAUCCUUUAAAUGCAAAAAAGUAAAAUAUAUAGAAUUAAAACCAAAGUGAAUUAUAUUAAAAAUUAUUAAACUAUUUAAGUAUGUGAUAUAUUAAUAUAUUUGCUUUUUAGUCAACACAUCAUUAAAUAAGACCUAGCAGUAAGCCUAGUAAGUAUUGUCAUCUUGACUCAUGUGGACCAUAAAUGGUAUUUGAAAAUAUUUUCAACAACUUUCACGGGCUGUGAAAGUAUUUGUAAUUUCUACUGGGAAAUCACAAAUCACAGGGUUUGUGAAGAUGCCAUGGUUUGUUGCUGCAUUCACAUUGCAACUGAAGGAAAUGCUAAGUUUCAGUUACAGGUUGGUGAAAAUAAAGAUGUAACUUUUUCUCAUUCAAGUUCACAGAUCCUCUUAAUUCUGCCUGUUCUAGCAAGUGAAGUGAGAGGAAAUUAACAUGUAAUGAUUGGCCCCAACUACCACUGCCUGACACUGAAUAGGCCCUGAGGAAAUGUUGGUAGCAUUGAAAGCACUUGGGAAACUAUAAAACUCCAUUCAGAUAUGAAGGCUUGUGAUUAUUACAGCUAUCAUUUUUAUUAGUGUGAAGGAGAGCACACAGAAGAGCUUGGCUACUAUCUUUAAUCACUUGAAGGACUUUCAAGCCGAAAAAGGAUUAUAUCUUGUGGAUGAGUUGGUGGAUGCUGAAGAGAACCCCUCCCUCCCUAAUCCAUUCUCCGUGUGGCUUCUGAGUUAAUUUUCCUAAUGACAGUUUAUAAUCAUGACACUUUCAUGAAACCCCCAUGGAACCUUUCUGUGGUUCCUCAUUAUCUCUGGGCCACUGUCCAUCUGUUCGGCCCUUCUCAGUCUGGCUCCAACCCAUCCCUAGGGCUGCAGACCUACCACUCUCUCCAGGCCCUGUCCACCUGGGCUAAGCCAGAACACCCUGAACUGUGCCGUGAUCCUUGCUCCCAGCAAAUGUUUUCUCUGUAAAUCUGUGUAUUAAAAUUCUGCCAAUCCUUCCAAGCUUAGAUCUAAAUCUCUCUUCUUCACAAAAUUUUCCAGGAGCUCUCUGUGGUGCAAAGCCAGAGAGUACACAGCAUGAACCUGAGCCUCCUCUCUUGGGUUUUGUUUGACCAAGUCCAAGGCAGGUUCCAUUAUCUUUGUCCCAGGUGUUUUAAGGGGAGGCUCUUGGAAUUCAGACAUAGGCCUGCCUGAUUCUAGAGGCCUGCACUUUUCAACCAGACCAUCUUGUUCCAAGCCAUGCUCUUUCUCUCCCACUCUCUUACAGCACUGGUCUCCAGCACUGACUCAUGGAGGAGGAUUUGUACUUUUCCCCCUCUAGCCUGGAACCUUCCCAGGGCAGAGGACUUUUUCCAGCAUUUUGUAUAUCCAUGGGACCUUGAGUUUGGUGACUAUGUAUUAAUUGAUUUGGGGACUGACAGACUUGCUUCCUCUUUUCCUAGCUCCCAGUCUUGGGGGUGUCCAUGGUUUGUCCCUAGGAGUGUUCCAACAUUUGAGUGUGGUCUCCUGGUUGGUGAGAUUCACUUGGAGCCUAGCCUGGCAGAUGGAGUUAGAAGCCACCAUUCCUGCUCUUCCCCAAGGCGUUUCCCAGCUUCAAAGGCUCCCUUCAGGUAGAGGGAGGAAGUUUCACUUAUUGUCUCCCCUGUCUGGGAAAGUGGCAGUGCAGAUCAUCUCUCCCAAAAAGAAUGGAUUUUUCCUGAAUGAAGCAGCUGUCAGUAGGUUGCCAGGCUUGUUUAAUGCUUGGGUGUUUUCAGGCUGUCUGGGAAUGAGAUUCUAGGAUGACUAGCUGUUUAACCCUCCCAGAGAAGCAGAGGCUGAGAGAAGGGUUGGCAAGGGUGCAGGGUCCUUUGAGGCUGCUGCACACUGAGGAGGGGGUGCUCUGAGCUACUGUAGGGUUCAUGUCCUGUAGACUUUCUGGGGGCCCUGGGGAGGUAAGGGUGUCUCUUCUCUCUCUGCCGCUCUCUGUUGUGUUUUGGUUUCUGCUUUGCUCUCUUUCUAGGGUUUGCCUUCUCUCUUAGCAGUUUCUCUUUCUUCUUUC